AUGGUCGGGGACAGUGGGGGUGGUGGGCCCUGGGCAGUAGGGGUGGUGGUGUUAGUGAAAGCUCUUGCCUUUUUCUGGGGCACCGUCUUCUCCUUCUCGUCACCCCGGGCAGUGCCCCUGGGCUCCUCGGCUGCUGCGGGCCUGGGCCACCCGUGUCAGCGCGGCCCUGCUGACAGCGCAGUUCACACCCGGGGCGGCCGCGGCAGGUGCAGUGCGAGGGGCGCCACCUGUAGGCUGGUGUGGGCACUGCCUAGAGGUUGCUGUGGCGCCGUCUGGAGGUUGCCGUGGCUCUCGUUGGCGCCCAGCGCCGCGCCCGGGGCUUCAUGGCUGUGUCGCUGCUGCCCCCUCCCAGGGCCGCAGGGCCCGGGUUCCACUUGGCGGCGUCUUCUCGCGAGUCGCUUUCGCUGCUCCAAGAAGUCGGCGGUGCAGCAACUGACGCCGCUGCUGCUCCGGUCGCCGCAGGUCGCCAUAUUCCUCGCGGGGGCCGGCCGGGCUCUCGGCUCAGGCCGCCCACCCUGCUCCGGCCGCCGCCGCCUCUCCGUUCCCGCAGCCAGAGGAGGCGAGGGAGCGACCUCCAGGCACUGGGCGCCCGCCGCUUCCCCAGCAGCCGGCGGGGCGGGGAAGAAAGACGCCAGGAAGCGGAAGGCCCCCGCCGGCCCGAGGGUCGCCCGGGGCUGUGCCCCAUGGUUCCUGGCCCGCGAGCAGCUGCUGGGACCCCCCCUUGCCAAGUUGCUCCCCGAAAAGCUCUAAGGUUCUCAGGCCUGCAGGGAGUGACAGUUUCCCCCUGACUGUAACGUAUGAUCUCGUGAAACCUUGAGAGAAACUGAAUGACGAAUGAAACUAUUGUUCCUGUUUCACACAGAAGAAAACUGAGGUUAAAAGGGG